AGUCCUGGGCAGCUCGGCAGUCCAGCCCGGCCCGGGUCAUGGUGGUGGGCCGAGGGCUGCUCGGCCGCCGCAGCCUCGCCGCGCUGGGAGCCGCCUGCGCCCGCCGAGGCCUCGGUCCAGCCCUGCUGGGAGUUUUCUGCCACACAGAUUUGCGGAAGAACCUGACCGUGGACGAGGGCACCAUGAAGGUAGAGGUGCUGCCUGCCCUGACCGACAACUACAUGUACCUGGUCAUUGAUGAUGAGACCAAGGAGGCUGCCAUUGUGGAUCCGGUGCAGCCCCAGAAGGUCGUGGACGCGGCGAGAAAGCACGGGGUGAAACUGACCACAGUGCUCACCACCCACCACCACUGGGACCAUGCUGGCGGGAAUGAGAAACUGGUCAAGCUGGAGUCGGGACUGAAGGUGUACGGGGGUGACGACCGUAUCGGGGCCCUGACUCACAAGAUCACUCACCUGUCCACACUGCAGGUGGGGUCUCUGAACGUCAAGUGCCUGGCGACCCCGUGCCACACUUCAGGACACAUUUGUUACUUCGUGAGCAAGCCCGGAGGCUCGGAGCCCCCUGCCGUGUUCACAGGUGACACCUUGUUUGUGGCUGGCUGCGGGAAGUUCUAUGAAGGGACUGCGGAUGAGAUGUGUAAAGCUCUGCUGGAGGUCUUGGGCCGGCUCCCCCCGGACACAAGAGUCUACUGUGGCCACGAGUACACCAUCAACAACCUCAAGUUUGCACGCCACGUGGAGCCCGGCAAUGCCGCCAUCCGGGAGAAGCUGGCCUGGGCCAAGGAGAAGUACAGCAUCGGGGAGCCCACAGUGCCAUCCACCCUGGCAGAGGAGUUUACCUACAACCCCUUCAUGAGAGUGAGGGAGAAGACGGUGCAGCAGCACGCAGGUGAGACGGACCCGGUGACCACCAUGCGGGCCGUGCGCAGGGAGAAGGACCAGUUCAAGAUGCCCCGGGACUGAGGCCGCCCUGCACCUUCAGCGGAUUUGGGGAUUAGGCUCUUUUAGGUAACUGGCUUUCCUGCUGGUCCGUGCGGGAAAUUCAGUCUUGAUUUAACCUUAAUUUUACAGCCCUUGGCUUGUGUUAUCGGACAUUCUAAUGCAUAUUUAUAAGAGAAGUUUAACAAGUAUUUAUUCCCAUAACUUCCCCUUGCAGACUGUUUUCUUCUGGCCUUUAGGCCUCUGCUUGUCCCCUCGGGCCUCCUUCCUCCUCCGUGAGCCACUGCAGUCCCCCCACCCACGCUUCAGGUCAGGCGUGAGCCGGUGCCUUUGCUGUGGCCUUGGCUGGGUGCUGAUGGGACUGUCAGGCCCACUGCUGCGGUCGGUACCUUUGCAGCCUGUGCUUGUGGUCUGAUCUGCUCAGGCCCCCGGCAGGGAGAGGUGGCCGCGUCUUCUUCCUGGAGGCGGCCAGAUCGCGCGACCUCCAGGCAGUGCUCCUACUCGGCAGCACCCACCUGCCUCUGCUUGAGAAAGCACAAACCGCCCUCUGGGGAAGCAGCCAGCUGGGGAGUGCUCUCGGCCUGUGACCCCGGGAGGGCUGGGUAGGUGGCCACAUGUCCUGCCCCGGCUCUGGGUGUGGCUGGUGGCAGAGGGUCUAUGAGGGAAGGGCAGGACAAAGGCAACCCCUAAGGCUAAUCUGAAAUUUAGGGCUGGGCGUGGUGGCUAAGCCUGUGAUCCCAGCACUUUGGGAGGCCGAGGCGGGUGGAUCACGAGGUCAGGAGAUCGAGUCCAUCCUGGCUAACAUGGUGAAACCCCGUCUCUACUAAAAAUACAAAAAAUUAGCCAGGUGUGGUGGCAGACACCUGUAGUCCCGGCUACUCGGGAGGCUAAGGCAGGAGAAUGGUGUGAACCCAGGAGGCGGGGCUUGCAGUGAGCCGAGAUAGCGCCACUGCACUCCAGCCUGGGAGACAGAGCAAGACUCUGUCUCAAAAAAAAAAAAAUAUGAAAUUUAAUAAUAAUCUUUUUAAAAAGUUACCUGGGCAGGGUGGUGUGCAGCUGUAGUCCUAGCUACUCAGGAGGCUGAGGCAGGAGGAUCGCUUGAGCCCGGGAGUCCAAGGCUGCAGUGAGCAUUGCUUGUGCCACUGCAUUCUGGCUUGGGGAACAGGGAGACCCUGUCUCAAAGAAAUUAAUUAAUCAUGCAGUUGAGUGGUAUUUAGUCCAUUCACAAUGCUGCAGCCGCCUCUCGCGUGUUCUGAAACAUUUGACCUAUUCACUGACUGACUGACUGCUCUGUCAGUGAGCUGUGAGGGGAGGUGACUCUGUGUGGGGCCCACACCCUCUGCCACCUGGUCCUAUAGACAGACUCUUCUGAGUGGAGGGGCAGAGCGGCCCUGGGACCUAGGAGCAAGCCUGGCCCGAGGCUUGUGGAUUGAAGAGGAAGGCUGGCACUGCACUUCAGACCACAUGCAUGCCCUCCCCCCGGAGGGGUCACUGGUCUGUUCGCAUACUCGCAGACCCCUCUGGGAUGCCACGGAAGCCAGGCGUGUGUGAGGAGGCAGGGCAGACUGCUUCUCCGGCUUUCUUCUCCCACUACCCCCGCCCCAGCGCAAAGAGUUUGUUCUAUUGUUCAGCAAAUAUUCUUAGGCCAGAAUCUUAAAUGUUUCCAUUCUAUAACAAA